AGAUCGCCGAAGCGUCGGACUACCGUUGGUUUCCGCAACUUCCUGGAUUAUCCUCGCCAAGGACUUUGCAAUAUAUUUUUCCGCCUUUUCUGGAAGGAUUUCGCUGCUUCCCGAAGGUCUUGGACGAGCGCUCUAGCUCUGUGGGAAGGUUUUGGGCUCUCUGGCUCGGAUUUUGCAAUUUCUCCCUGGGGACUGCCGUGGAGCCGCAUCCACUGUGGAUUAUAAUUGCAACAUGACGCUGGAAGAGCUCGUGGCGUGCGACAACGCGGCGCAGAAGAUGCAGACGGUGACCGCCGCGGUGGAGGAGCUUUUGGUGGCCGCUCAGCGCCAGGAUCGCCUCACAGUGGGGGUGUACGAGUCGGCCAAGUUGAUGAAUGUGGACCCAGACAGCGUGGUCCUCUGCCUCUUGGCCAUUGACGAGGAGGAGGAGGAUGACAUCGCCCUGCAAAUCCACUUCACGCUCAUCCAGUCCUUCUGCUGUGACAACGACAUCAACAUCGUGCGGGUGUCGGGCAUGCAGCGCCUGGCGCAGCUCCUGGGAGAGCCGGCCGAGACCCAGGGCACCACCGAGGCCCGAGACCUGCAUUGUCUCCUGGUCACGAACCCUCACACGGACGCCUGGAAGAGCCACGGCUUGGUGGAGGUGGCCAGCUACUGCGAAGAAAGCCGGGGCAACAACCAGUGGGUCCCCUACAUCUCUCUUCAGGAACGCUGAGGCCCUUCCCAGCAGCAGAAUCUGUUGAGUUGCUGCCACAAACAAAAAAUACAAUAAAUAUUUGAACCCCCUCCCCCCCAGCACAACCCCCCCAAAACAACCCAACCCACGAGGACCAUCGGGGGCAGAGUCGUUGGAGACUGAAGAGGAAGAGGAGGAGGAGAAGGGGAGUGAGCGGCCGCCCCCAGGGCGGAGAUCCAGGAGCUGGCGGCCGCCGAUCCGAUGGAGAAGGGGGGACCCAGGCCAGCAGGAGACAGGACCCCCGAAGCUGAGGCCUUGGGAUGGAGCAGAAGCCGGAGUGGCGGGGCACGCUGCCGCCUUCCCCAUCACGGAGGGUCCAGACUGUCCACUCGGGGGUGGAGUGAGACUGACUGCAAGCCCCACCCUCCUUGAGACUGGAGCUGGCGUCUGCAUACGAGAGACUUGGUUGAACUUGGUUGGUCCUUGUCUGCACCCUCGACAAGACCACACUUUGGGACUUGGGAGCUGGGGCUGAAGUUGCUCUGUACCCAUGAACUCCCAGUUUGCGAAUUAUAGAGACAAUCUAUUUUGUUACUUGCACUUGUUAUUCGAACCACUGAGAGCGAGAUGGGAAGCAUAGAUAUCUAUAUUUUUAUUUCUACUAUGAGGGCCUUGUAAUAAAUUUCUAAAGCCUC